AUGUGGAUGCUGGGAGAAGUAUGUGAGAUGGAAAAGUUGUUUCAUGGCAUCCAAGAAGUGAAUGAUCCUCAAGGUGUAGCAGAGGAAUCUGUAGGAGAGAGGGAUGAUUGACGUCUUCGUAUAGCCCUCCAUCCAUCCCAGUUAGCAUGGAGGGAUUUUAGGGCUACCAUUGGCUGGGUAGUGGAGUGUUGACCAAUCACAGCUCAGGGGCGUGAUUGUCUCGUCCUGGGAUCGCGAGAGGGGUAUAUACAGGGAGGCCAGGCAGCCUGGAGUUAGUCGACCGUUGCGAGACGUUGAGCUGCGGAAGAUGAGUCCAAAGCCGAGAGCCUCGGGACCUCCGGCCAAGGCCACGGAGGCAGGAAAGAGGAAGUCCUCCUCUCAGCCGAGCCCCAGUGACCCGAAGAAGAAGACUACCAAGGUGGCCAAGAAGGGAAAAGCAGUUCGUAGAGGGAGACGCGGGAAGAAAGGGGCUGCGACAAAGAUGGCGGCCGUGACGGCACCUGAGGCGGAGAGCGGGCCAGCGGCACCCGGCCCCAGCGACCAGCCCAGCCAGGAGCUCCCUCAGCACGAGCUGCCGCCGGAGGAGCCAGUGAGCGAGGGGACCCAGCACGACCCCCUGAGUCAGGAGAGCGAGCUGGAGGAACCACUGAGUCAGGAGAGCGAGGUGGAAGAACCACUGAGUCAGGAGAGCCAGGUGGAGGAACCACUGAGUCAGGAGAGCGAGGUGGAAGAACCACUGAGUCAGGAGAGCCAGGUGGAGGAACCACUGAGUCAGGAGAGCGAGGUGGAGGAACCACUGAGUCAGGAGAGCCAGGUGGAGGAACCACUGAGUCAGGAGAGCGAGAUGGAAGAACUACCGAGUGUGUAGACGGCCAGCUACUCCCCUAUCUCCGAGAGCAGCGACUAAGUUCAGGCCCAGCCGCCAGACCUCAGAGAUCUCACCAGCGGGGUGCUUGCCAUUCUGAAGAUAAUAAAAUGAAUGUGUUGCAAAUUGA